AUUGGCGUCGGCCGCGCUGUAUUGUCAUAAAUAGAGCCGGUUUUGUGGUGUUUUCACUACUCGGUUGGAUGCCUCAGCCAUAGUAAGUGGGAAAGUGAGCGAGCAAGCGAGCUACUAGCGACCGGAGGAAAGUGAACAGGGGGAGAAGGGAACAGCAAGAACAGGACUCCAGAGCGAUAAACACUCGCUGGAGAGGGAGACGCAGGAAGCGAUGAAAGAGAUGUCUGCAAACACCGUGCUGGACAGCCAGCGUCAACAAAAGCAUUAUGGAAUUACCUCCCCAAUUAGUUUGGCAUCUCCUAAAGAAAUUGAUCAUAUUUACACACAGAAAUUAAUUGACGCCAUGAAACCAUUUGGAGUGUUUGAAGAUGAGGAAGAAUUGAACCACAGGCUGGUGGUUCUUGGUAAAUUGAACAAUUUAGUAAAAGAAUGGAUUUCUGAUGUCAGCGAGAGUAAGAACCUCCCACCUUCUGUUGUGGCUACUGUUGGUGGUAAAAUUUUCACAUUUGGAUCCUAUAGGCUUGGAGUACACACCAAAGGAGCUGACAUUGAUGCACUUUGUGUAGCUCCAAGACAUGUGGAAAGAUCUGAUUUUUUUCAGUCUUUUUUUGAAAAAUUGAAACAUCAAGAUGGCAUUAGAAACUUAAGAGCUGUAGAAGAUGCCUUUGUACCUGUUAUAAAAUUUGAAUUUGAUGGUAUUGAAAUUGAUCUAGUCUUUGCAAGACUGGCAAUACAAACCAUAUCAGAUAAUUUAGAUCUAAGAGACGACUCUCGCCUGAGAAGCCUUGAUAUAAGGUGUAUUCGCAGCUUAAAUGGUUGUAGAGUUACUGAUGAAAUUUUGCAUUUAGUGCCAAAUAAAGAAACUUUUAGACUCACCCUAAGAGCUGUCAAAUUAUGGGCAAAACGACGUGGUAUUUAUUCCAACAUGCUAGGAUUCCUUGGUGGUGUCUCCUGGGCAAUGCUAGUUGCAAGAACUUGCCAAUUGUAUCCAAAUGCAGCAGCAUCUACUUUAGUUCAUAAGUUCUUUUUAGUUUUUUCCAAGUGGGAAUGGCCAAAUCCUGUGCUGCUGAAGCAACCAGAAGAAAGCAAUUUGAAUUUGCCUGUCUGGGAUCCUCGGGUAAAUCCAUCAGAUAGGUAUCAUCUCAUGCCCAUAAUCACCCCUGCCUACCCACAACAGAAUUCUACGUAUAAUGUGUCCACAUCAACUCGAACAGUAAUGGUAGAAGAAUUUAAACAAGGUCUUGCAGUCACAGAUGAAAUUCUUCAAGGAAAGUCAGAUUGGUCCAAACUACUUGAGCCACCGAAUUUCUUUCAAAAGUAUAGACAUUAUAUAGUAUUGACUGCCAGCGCAUCAACAGAAGAAAACCAUCUAGAGUGGGUUGGAUUAGUAGAAUCUAAAAUCCGUGUACUUGUUGGAAACUUGGAACGGAAUGAAUUUAUUACUCUUGCCCAUGUGAAUCCCCAGUCAUUCCCAGGGAAUAAGGAACAUCAUAAAGACAACAAUUACGUAUCAAUGUGGUUCCUUGGGAUAAUUUUUCGGAGAGUAGAAAAUGCAGAAAGUGUCAACAUAGACUUGACAUAUGAUAUACAGUCAUUUACUGAUACAGUGUACAGACAGGCAAACAAUAUAAAUAUGCUAAAGGAGGGAAUGAAAAUUGAAGCAACUCAUGUAAAGAAAAAACAACUUCACCACUACCUUCCUGCAGAAAUUCUUCAAAAGAAGAAAAAGCAAAGUCUCUCUGAUGUCAAUCGAAGCUCGGGCGGACUUCAAUCCAAAAGAUUGUCUCUGGAUAGCAGUUGUCUGGAUAGCUCCAGAGACACUGAUAAUGGAACACCUUUUAAUUCUCCAGCGUCCAAGUCUGAUAGCCCUUCUGUAGGAGAAACAGAAAGGAAUAGUGCUGAGCCUGCUGCUGUAAUUGUGGAGAAGCCACUGAGUGUACCACCAGCCCAAGGACUUUCCAUUCCAGUGAUUGGCGCAAAAGUUGACUCUACAGUAAAAACUGUAUCACCCCCCACUGUGUGUACCAUUCCUACCGUAGUAGGACGAAAUGUCAUUCCUAGAAUCACAACACCUCACAACCCUGCCCAGGGACAACCGCAUCUGAAUGGAAUGUCAAAUAUAACUAAGACUGUUACACCUAAGAGAUCCCAUUCCCCAUCCAUAGAUGGGACUCCUAAGAGGUUGAAAGACGUAGAAAAGUUUAUUCGACUUGAAUCAACAUUUAAGGACCCCCGCACUGCUGAAGAAAGAAAAAGAAAAUCAGUGGAUGCCAUUGGAGGAGAAUCUAUGCCUAUUCCAACUAUUGAUACAUCACGCAAAAAGAGACUACCCAGUAAAGAACUACCAGAUUCAUCAUCUCCAGUUCCAGCAAACAACAUCCGUGUCAUCAAAAAUUCCAUUCGACUGACCCUUAAUCGGUAAAAGCAGUGCCUCCUCACUUAAGUGAACAAGCAAUCAUUUAGUGGCAUAGAUGCAGCCACUUGUUUUUUAAAUAGAAGUGGCUGUCAUACGUGAAAUAAGGUGAAAGUGACAGCCUUCAGUCUAAUAACCUUGAAGUGGUUUUUGAACUGUCAAACUUUGACCUGUAGAUGCUGUAGCAUUCUCUCACUGAUUGCUACAUACACUUCUCUGAGGAUCACCUGCUGUCAAAUUGCCAUCUACAGUAUUACAGCUUUGCAUUUGGGGGUUUUACUGCCUUAACUUUCAAUGCUUGUUAUGGGAACCAGUUCUUAGCCACUUGGACACUGAUAACAAGUCCUGAACUCCUUUUUUGUUUUGUUUUUUGUGUUUUUCUUUUUUUGUCUUAUGUUGUAAUCAUUGUAUAGAGCUAAAAAAAUUGAAAACAAACAAAAAAAUUGUCUUGUAUUUUCCAAAUGUUAAUACAUUUACUUUAGCAUUGAAGCCACUUUGAAACCUGAGAUAAAUGAAUGUGAGGUAUCUUUUCUGCUUUCCUCAUUUGUGUAGAUGUACUGUCUGUUCUGUUGAUUUAAAUUAUUUUUUUCCAGAUUGGCACAUGAAAUAUUUAAACUUUUUUGUGUGCCUUUCUGUCCAAAUGUUGCAUAGUUACCAGGGAAGAUUAGUCCAGUGAUUACAUAAGAGUUGGGCACCAUAAAUUCUCUAUAUUUUGCCUCCCAUGGAGGCCUUUGAAAUGCAUCUUUAUUAAAAAUCAAAAUAUAACCAGGAUACUGAAAGUCAGUAUAUGAAUGGUAAAAUUGUUACAUAUCCUAUUUCAUGCCAUUCUUGUUAGUUGACUGGUAUUUUUUACUGAGGAGCAACUCAUUCCAGCAUCAACAAUAAGAUAACCUUUAAGUAUGGCACACUUGUAUUUUUGAGGUGUAAAAUUAACUUGGCAUGAUAAUUCCUGAUCAUUAUUUACCCCACAACUUCAAAUAGUUUCUUCACGGACUAGGCAUGCAGAAAUAAGCAGUGGAUUUUAUUGAAACCUAAAGGCAUUUUGAAUGACAUUGUUACCAACCAUUAAUUGGCUCAGGACCUUUGUAAUUUUUAUUUAACUAUAUGAGUUGUCUUUUUUUACGCUGCUUUUUUCAAUGCAUUUCUUAAUAUUUUUUAAGUUUCAUGAAUGCAUGCUCAGUUUAUUAAAAUCCAUAACCAUGUAAUUCUUGUAAUAUGUUGAUUCAGUGUUUUGUAAAUGAAGUCGUAUGUAUUUUCAGAGUAUUUUUGUAUGUACUGUAAGAUACCAUCUUUUCAAAGAGAAACGUUUAAAACCUUUAUUGUCUCUCCUUAGUCUAAUUUUUUAAAUAUGGAUUAUGCUUGAAUUACUAUAUUUAAAAUGAAAAUGUAUAGAUUACACAGCCAGGAAUGCUAGUAUCUACCACCUUCUUUAGAUUUCACUCAGCAUUUAGUAGGUCCAGUAGGAAAAACCCAAAAUGGUACAUUGAGUAGUGUGGGGAAGACACCUCGUGUAUUAUAGGACUCACGGGAUGCCAUCUAGCAAGUGGAGAAAUAGCAGUCCAUUUUCUCUUGCAAGCCCUUUACCAUUGAGUUGAAAUUCUUGAAUUGCCAGAGAGCCGUAUCCUCCAGGUCCCACUCCUGUUCAUUGCCCCUUAGGUCUCCAAAAUGUAAAUUCUAAUGUUUACCUUGUACCAUGGAAAACAUGAAAAGAGUCUUAGAAGUAAAGAACAACAAGGAAAAAAAUGUUUGUUCUAUUAUUCCCUUUUUAUAUAGCAGCAAAAGAUAAGAAUAAAAUCACAUAACCAAGUUGAAGCUUCCUUGGCAAAGCUGUUGUCUUAGCUGACUCUUUCCCUUUAUUCAGAUGUUUUGGGAUUGUUCUACAAAUAGUCUAUUUGAGCAAAAAUGAAUGAUUAUGAAAGAACCGAAGAAUUAUCACCUGACUUCAACUUUUGAAAGCUUUAGUAAGGAAUUUGAUUAAAUUUUAUAUACUGGAUGUGUAUGCAUUUCUGCAUUUCAUAUCUUUUGCUUUUAAAUCAGCCUUCAAAGUAUCUUUAGGAAUUCCUUCUGUAUCCAUGUUUACCCCAUUAUGUAAAUAGAUCUUUGGAGUGACUAGUGGAGUUUUUCUUUAAUAAGGAAGCAACAAGUCUAACCUUGUACUAUAGGAUAGGCAUUUAUUUUAGAUUAAGGAGCCCAUUCAACAUGUCAAUGAGUCAACAUUAGAGUCCUCAAAGAUAGCAUUCUUCAACCUGUUUGGUAACUGAGGAGUUGAUAAAAUACUUUUGAGAUGGUGGGGUUUGUCAGAAAUAAAAUAUUUUCUAUCCUGACCAGUAGGUAGAACUUUGAGUACAUUUCGUUAACUUGGUGGGAAGCUUCCAUUGUACUAGUUCCAAGUAAAAAAGGAGAAAGUAUGAUCUGGGAUUUUGUGUUAUGAUGAGAGGCACUAAGUACAUGUGUUUGUUUUGUUUUGUUUUGUUUUGUUUUGUUUUGUUUGAGACAGAGUUUUGCUCUUGUUGCCCAGGCUGGAGUGCAGUAGCCCAAUCUCGGCUCACUGCAACCUUCACCUCCCGAGUUCAAGCUAUUCUCUUGCCUCAGCCUCCCAAGUAGCUGGGAUUACAGGCACCCACCACCUCGCCCAGCUAAUUUUUGUAUUUUUAGUACAGACAGCGUUUCACCAUGUUGGCCAGGCUGGUCUCGAACUUGUGACCUCAGGUGAUCCACCUGCCUCGGCGUCCCAAAGUGCUGGGAUUACAGGCGUGAACCACCGCACCCGGCCGUGUUUGUUUUCAAGUGUGAAAAAAUACCUAGAAGUAUAUUUUAUGAAGUCAAAUAAUCUGUUCUUCAGUAUAUAGACACAUGUUCAUUUUCACAAGGGCAUUACAUUUUAAUUUGCUCAUUUUUCAGUAGCUCUGGAGAAUAUGUAUGAAAGGAAAACAAUUACCUGCUAGCUUAAACCUUAGGGACUUAACCAAUUCAAGAUAGAGGUACAUGGCUUAAAACUUUGUAAAACUGGGACAGGAGAAUUAUUAUUUUUUUAUUUUUUAUUUUUUUAUGAAGACAAGAGUUUCACUCUGUCACCCAGUCUGGAGCACAGUGGCAUGAUCUCACCUCACUGCAACCUCUGCCUCCCGGGUUCAAGUGAUUCUCUUGCCUCAGCCUCCCAAGUAGCUGGAAUUACAGGCCUGUGCCAUGCCCAGCUAAUUUUCGUAUUUUCAGUAGAAAUGGGAUUUCACCAUGUUGGCCAGGGUGGUCUUGAACUCCUCACCUCAAGUGAUCUGGCUGCUUCGGCCACCCUAAGUGCUGGGAUUACAGGCAUAAGCUACUGUGCCCAGCCAGGAGAAUGAAUUUUAAAAAUCUAUGUUAGUGUUUAAAAUGAGUGCUUUGUUUUAAAGCAGCAAUUUAGUAGCAUUAUUAAAAUGCUUACUUCACUAUAGUAGCAAUUAGGUAAAGAUGGGCAAUAUCAAAAUGGGCUAAACUUAUUUUCCACUAUGUUCCACACCUUUGAAAUAGGAAUUCCUAACUUGAGAAUCAUGAACCCUUAGGGAAUCCUUUAUAAUUGUGUAUAAGAAGUUCUAGUUUACAUGCAUUUUUCUUGGGGAAAGUGCAUAGUUUAGAUCAGCUUCUCGAAGUGGCAAAAGUAUGGGAGUUAGGGUUAGGAACCACCAGGAUUGAAUAAUCCUGGAAUAUUAUAUAAUUUUCUACUUUUGAUUUUGCUGUGGUAUAUUUCUGAAAAUGUGCUGUGGCUCCUAACUAGUAAAAUGGGCUGGUGAGGGACUCUGGAAUUCUGAAUUUCUAAGUUUAUAACCUAAAAUGAAACUGUAAAGUCCUCGGUAUUUAGAAAAAUGCUUAAUCUCAGAUUUACAGAUGGCCUCAUGAUAACUUAGAUUCGUUAACAGGGUCAAACUUUAGUUCAACAAAUUUCAACCCAAUAUUAUCACAGUACAAUAGCUUAGAAUGAUCAUUAGAAAUGGUAGAAAAUAGAAUAAAUCAUUAAAGAUCCCAAAAUGUUGAGUUCUGUAGCAUGAAAACUCUCUUGCUCCUCCAUGUUUGUAGUUCAGGCCAGAACAAACUAAACAGACCAAUAAAUAUAAAAGUGAUAGUUUAGGGAAAAAAAAAAACUUUGUAUAAAUAAAAUUGUAUGUGUGUUCAAAUAACUACCUAUUAAAUCAUCCAAAGCUUAGAAUUUAAAUUGGUCAUAGUAGCAAAUAGUGCAGAUGAUGGAAGAAAACCAGUCUCAAUAAUGGUUUUUUUUUUCCAAUUGCAUAAGGUCACGUCAUCCCCCAAAUUGUCUAUUUUUUCUUUUCUUUUUUUUUAAGAUGGAGUCUCGCUCCGUCACCCAGGCUGGAAUGCAGUGGCGCAAUCUUGGCUCAUUGCAACCUCCACCUCCCAGGUGCAAGCGAUUCUCCUACCUCAGCCUCCCAAGUAGCUGGGACUACAGGCGCCCGCCACCAUGUGGGCCUGGCUAAUUUUUGUAGAGAUGGGGUUUCAACAUGUUGGCCAGGCUGGUCUCAAACUCCUGACCUCCAGUGAUGCACCCGCCUCGGCCUCCCAAAGUUCUGGGAUUACAGGCGUGAGCCACCGUGCCCAGCCCCUAUUUUUUCUGAAAUAAUUUUUCGGAUAUACUUUUAUAUUUGAAAUUAGUUGAACAUAAGAUGAUCAUCAAGCUUGCUAUAAGUUUUAAGCUAUUGCUACAUUUGAACAAAGACCCACGUACUUAUCUUAGAAAGUACUUAGGAUAUCUUUGAGAUUAAUGGUGCUACAUCACUCUACAGUACUAUGUAAAAUGAAUGGAGCUGCUGUUCCUUUCUAGCUAGCUGUUUGUGUAGUUCAUAUUAAUUUACCCUGCCUUUUAUUUGGAUUGUCUGAUUUCUUAGUUGUACACAUGAACCUCAUUAUUUGCCUGGAAUAAGUAAUCAAAUAAAAUUGCUUUGAUAAAUA